ACUCGGCUCUCCCCGCUCCGCCCCCUGCCCCUGGCUCCCGUACGGUGGACGGCGACGCUGGGUGACCCGGGGUGCAAGAAUUCAGGGGUUGGGAAGGUGUGAGCCGCAAACCCAGCGGAGGGCGGGAAGAAGGAGGAGGCCUCUAGGGUGGUCGGGGGACUGGGGGCCCCGCCGGCAGAGGUCCCUCGGCCUCCUGACUGACUGACUGCGGCCGCCUCCGGCCAGGACGCUGGGAGCUGCCUGCGGGAAGGUGCGGGGAGCGGAGCCAUGGCCUCCGGUGCGUAUAACCCGUAUAUAGAGAUAAUUGAACAACCCAGGCAGAGGGGAAUGCGUUUUAGAUACAAAUGUGAAGGGCGAUCAGCAGGCAGCAUUCCAGGGGAGCACAGCACAGACAACAACCGAACAUACCCUUCUAUCCAGAUUAUGAACUAUUAUGGAAAAGGAAAAGUGAGAAUUACAUUAGUAACAAAGAAUGACCCAUAUAAACCUCAUCCUCAUGAUUUAGUUGGAAAAGACUGCAGAGACGGCUACUAUGAAGCAGAAUUUGGACAAGAACGCAGACCUUUGUUUUUCCAAAAUUUGGGUAUUCGAUGUGUGAAGAAAAAAGAAGUAAAAGAAGCUAUUAUUACAAGAAUAAAGGCAGGAAUCAAUCCAUUCAAUGUCCCUGAAAAACAGCUGAAUGAUAUUGAAGAUUGUGACCUCAAUGUGGUGAGACUGUGUUUUCAAGUUUUUCUCCCUGAUGAACAUGGUAAUUUGACGACUGCUCUUCCUCCUGUUGUCUCGAACCCAAUUUAUGACAACCGUGCUCCAAAUACUGCAGAAUUAAGGAUUUGUCGUGUAAACAAGAAUUGUGGAAGUGUCAGAGGAGGAGAUGAAAUAUUUCUACUUUGUGACAAAGUUCAGAAAGAUGACAUAGAAGUUCGUUUUGUGUUGAACGAUUGGGAAGCAAAAGGCAUCUUUUCACAAGCUGAUGUACACCGUCAAGUAGCCAUUGUUUUCAAAACUCCACCAUAUUGCAAAGCUAUCACAGAACCCGUAACAGUAAAAAUGCAGUUGCGGAGACCUUCUGACCAGGAAGUUAGUGAAUCUAUGGAUUUUAGAUAUCUGCCAGAUGAAAAAGAUACUUACGGCAAUAAAGCAAAGAAACAAAAGACAACUCUGCUUUUCCAGAAACUGUGCCAGGAUCACGUAGAAACAGGGUUUCGCCAUGUUGACCAGGAUGGUCUUGAACUCCUGACAUCAGGUGAUCCACCCACCUUGGCCUCCCAAAGUGCUGGGAUUACAGUUAAUUUUCCUGAGAGACCAAGACCUGGUCUCCUCGGUUCAAUUGGAGAAGGAAGAUACUUCAAAAAAGAACCAAACUUGUUUUCUCAUGAUGCAGUUGUGAGAGAAAUGCCUACAGGGGUUUCAAGUCAAGCAGAAUCCUACUAUCCCUCACCUGGGCCCAUCUCAAGUGGAUUGUCACAUCAUGCCUCAAUGGCACCUCUGCCUUCUUCAAGCUGGUCAUCAGUGGCCCACCCCACCCCACGCUCAGGCAAUACAAACCCACUGAGUAGUUUUUCAACAAGGACACUUCCUUCUAAUUCGCAAGGUAUCCCACCAUUCCUGAGAAUACCUGUUGGGAAUGAUUUAAAUGCUUCUAAUGCUUGCAUUUACAACAAUGCCGAUGACAUAGUCGGAAUGGAAGCGUCAUCCAUGCCAUCAGCAGAUUUAUAUGGUAUUUCUGAUCCCAACAUGCUGUCUAAUUGUUCUGUGAAUAUGAUGACAACCAGCAGUGACAGCAUGGGAGAGACUGAUAAUCCAAGACUUCUGAGCAUGAAUCUUGAAAACCCCUCAUGUAAUUCAGUGUUAGACCCAAGAGACUUGAGACAGCUCCAUCAGAUGUCCUCUUCCAGUAUGUCAGCAGGCGCCAAUUCCAAUACUACUGUUUUUGUUUCACAAUCAGAUGCAUUUGAGGGAUCUGACUUCAGUUGUGCAGAUAACAGCAUGAUAAAUGAGUCGGGACCAUCAAACAGUACUAAUCCAAACAGUCAUGGUUUUGUUCAAGAUAGUCAGUAUUCAGGUAUUGGCAGUAUGCAAAAUGAGCAAUUGAGUGACUCCUUUCCAUAUGAAUUUUUUCAAGUAUAACUUGCAAGAUUUAAAUCCUUUUAAAUCUUGAUACCACCUAUAUAGAUGCAGCAUUUUGUAUUUGUCUAACUGGGGAUAUAAUACUAUAUUUAUACUGUAUAUAUAAUACUGACUGAGAAUAUAAUACUGUAUUUGAGAAUAUAAAAAACUUUUUUCAGGGAAGAAGCAUACAACUUUGGACAUAGCGAAUACAAAAUUGGAAGCUGUCAUAAAAAGACAACUCAGAGGCCAGGCGCAGGGGCUCACACCUGUAAUCCUAGCACUUUGGGAGGCCAAGGCGGGUGGAUCACUUGAGACCAGGAAUUCGAGACCAGCCUGGCCAACAUGGUGAAACCCCGUCUCUACUAAAAAUACAAAAAUUAGCUGAGCAUGGUGGUACGUGCCUGUACUGUCAGCUACUUGGGAGGCUGAGGCACAAUAAUUGUUUGAACCCAGGAAGCAGAGGUUGCAGUGAGCUGAGAUCACACCACCGCACUCCAGCCUGGGUGACAGAGUGAGACUCUGUCUCAAAAAAAAAAAAACAAAAAAAACACACUUUUUUAUAUUUCUUUUUAUAAUGUUUUAAUGUAUUCUUAAAUUUCAAGCAAAUUUAAGAUAAAACUUGUAAUGGCUAUGCCAUUGAAAAACUUAAUUUUUUAUUUUUGAGGCCCAUGGGCCAAGGUAACCCCUAAGGGGUUUUCUUAGGCUUCUUGGAGCUUAGAUUUGUAUGUAUAUCAAAAUGUCUUUAAAAUGUUAAGUUGGGCAGAAGGCAGUUGAAGUGAGCUUUCAAGGUAUGGGAGGUUUUCUACAUUUUAUACUAUUUCAAUCUAUGCCUUUAAAGUUGCUUAUGAUUUUAGCUGUACACUCAUUUUUUAAGGGGAAGAAGUUUCCUUGGACCAUUCGCCUUUCUUAGAUGUCCUCACUCCCUGUGAUCUCAUAAAACUGCCUAUUUGACAUCUCUAUCUAGAAAUCUAAUUAAAGCUCACACUCAGCAUAUCCAAAACUGAAUUCUUGGUCUUCCCUCCCAAACUUGCUUCUCCUUCAGUCUUCUCCAACUCAGUAAAUGGCAAUGCCAUACUUCUGGUUGCUCAGGCCAAAAACCCUGAAGUCAUCCUUGAUUCUUCUUUUAGCACCCAUAUCCAAUCCAUUAGCAAAUCUGGUAGACCCUACCUUCACAAUAUAUCUAAAGCUGACCACCUCUUUUGACCUCUACUAUUAACGCCCUAUUCCAAGCCACCAUCAUCUCUUCCCUGGAUUGAAGCUGUCAUCUACAAAAAUUCUUCUUAUAUCCUUGCAUUCCUACAGUCUGUUCCCCAUAAAGUAGCCAGAAUGAUUAUUUUUAAAACAAGUCAACUCAUACCAUUCAUCUGCUCAAAACCAUUCAUUGGCUUCUCAUCUCACUCAGAGCAGUCAAAGUCCUUAAAAGUUGCAGGCCUAGACUCCCUGUCCUACCUCAGGUACCACCAUAUCCCACCUCCUCAUGCAGCUCCAGGCACCUUGGCCUCAGUGCUCCUCAAAGCAUCAAGUAUGCACUUGCCUUGGACAGUCUGUACUUGGUAUUCCCUCUGCCUUGAAUGUUGUUCUCCCAGAAAAAUGCAUAGUUCACUCUUACAUCCUUCAGGUGUCACUCCACUGUUACCUGAGCAGGUCGUCCUUGAAUAUAUACAUCAGCAUUCCCUUUCCCCCCUGCUUUAUGUAUGUCCAUAGCACUCACCACGAUCUGACUUUACUAAGUAUUUAUUCAUUUACUGUUUGUUUUCCCAUACCGAAAUAUAAACUUUCUAAGGACAGAAAUUUUUGUGCUUUAUUGUUGAAUCUCCAAUUUGUAGAAAAAUGCCUACCUUAUAUUAAACACUCAGUAAAUGUUUAUUGAACAUUAAAAGUAUUACUAAUAGAACUUUGGUUUUUGAAAGAAAUAAUAACUUUAAUUAUAAGACGUAUAUGAUUUUUGCAGUUUUACUUAGUGUGACAUUGGGUUUAUGAGAAUCGUGUACAUUCAAGUCCAGGAAUAAUAAUGGUCAUCCAAAUUGUUUGAAAGGAAAAUAAUCCCAGUGGCAAAAUGAUGGUAGAAUUUGGGUAAUCUUUUUUUUCCUUUUAUGAAAAGAGAUUUUAUUGAAGGUAAAACAUUAGAGGUUCAUUGAGAAUCUCUAAAUCCAUGUUUUGACAUUGUCAAGCUCAUUGCAACUUCCAGAUUGAGUAACACUUAUAACACAUUUCCUUUUCAAAGUGCAAGAUUUUUAAAAGAGACUUGUCACAUAUUCAUUUGGCUGGUUUCAAAUGGUGAGCUGAAUGCUGGGUAAUCUCUACUAGCUCCUUAAUCAGAUUUAAAAUUCUCAGUGUUUCCUAGUUGUUUCUGCAUACUUUAUGUGAGUUGUUAUAGCUGUAACAUUACACUUUAUUUGCUGUUUGUGUUUCGUGACUUUUGGUAAUUCUGGCAUUUAGAAACCUUUCACUUUGCUUCAAAACGUAGUUAUAUUUUGGAGUUUUCAUUUGAUAUAUAAUUAUUUAUUUUGCCCUUUUAUUUCCCAAAGACAUUGUAAGGGUUAAUUAGAUCAUUAUAUUUUAUUAUUACAGAUUAAAGUUGGGCAGUAAUCUUAAUUAUGAUGGAAUUAUCAUUAUGCUAAGUAAUUAACUUUACCUAGUUUGUUUUACAACUAGAACCUGCCCUAAAUGUUGAAUAUCUUCCUAGCAAGAAACAGUCUGUCAUUUUACUUACACGAUGUCUAACCAAACCAUAACUUUACAUAAACUAGUCGUUUCGGUCAAAUAGAAAAAUGUGUGAAUGCCAUAAAAACAAAAAUUCUCAGUUAAAUGAUACUGGGAAAUAGGGAAGACAGCAAAGUGAGACUUGGGCUCAGGAUGGUUCAGGAAGAAAAAAAAAGAAAGACCCCUGAGUACCAUUAAUAUUCCUCAGAAAUUAUUAUUUCAAAAGGAAAUAUUUCUGUAUUAUAAAUUUUUCAUGAGCAGCCAUUAUGAAAUCUCACAAGAAUCAUAGAAUUCAAUAAAAAAGGUAGAAAGUAAUUUUUUUACUUAAAAAUAUAAAUUAAAAUAAAUUUUUAAAAUCAUAAGCACAUAAAUAGAACUUACCAGGGAGAAAGAAAAACCUGAAGGCACAAUUUCUUUUCUGUUCAAAAUGUGAACCCAGGAUGUCUCUAGAUGAUGAUGGAUGAUAGGUGGGGAGAUUUUUUUUUUUUUUAAUACAGAAUCUCAUAGUUUUGGAUUAAUUAGCACCAAUCAGUUUAAACACUGACUGUUAGAAUAGCUGCAUGGGUUUUUUUCUUUAAACUAAUUAAGCGUUGGCUACUUAGUAUAAGUAAGUAUAAGCCGAAUUAAGGUUCUGCUACAUCUGUGUUUAGAAUAUUUUUUUAAAACUAAAUAAGUGUUGGCUAGUUUUGCGGUGUAAGCAGAAUUAAGGUUCUGCUACCUCUGUGUGUAGAAUAUUCCCAAUGGAUUUUUCAUUUUUCAGGUGCUAUUUUUUGACCCUGUAUAGACUUUAAUUUAAAAUGAAUUUGGUAACGUUUCUCCUCUGUCUCUACAUAUAUUCAUGCUUUCACCUGCUCUUUUAACACCUGCUUUUAGUAUCUGAGGCACUUUUUCUGAACUCUACUUGUGCACUGGAUCCCUCCUCCUUUCUCUGCCAGGCUGUGUUUACUUUAUCCUUACAUCACCACUUAGUGAUUCCUUUCUUUGUAUAAACAUGGUAAAUGUCUUCAUUAGCCUAAAAGGAAAGACCAAAUAAAACCUUUCCUACCACUUGGAUGCAUUUGCAUCCUGACUUCUGAAAUGCCUCCAGCCUCCAUUUUCUCCCUUCCCAGUUAUUCCUUAGCCCAGCCAUCUCUGUCUUUAGCUCCUACAAUUUUCUUAGGAUAUUCUGGGAAAGAUGAGCGGAGACUGCCCGCCUUGUCAAAUCUAGUGUCUUUUUUUCAGUCCUCACACUGCUUGACCUAUGUAUAACCUCCUAUACUUCCCUCUUUGCAUACUCCUCUGGGUUUUCUGUGGUAGUCAAGAUUCCUCCCUGAGAUUUAUUUCCCAUGAGUCUUGACCCCUCCCCUCAGUUGGUGCUAUUUCCCCCUACCCGCCCUCCGAUGAUCUUAUCAGAGCCCACAGGUUCAGUUUUCUUUCAUGCUACCUGAAUGUCCUGAUAAACUGGCUCGCUCUCUUCUUUACCUUCCAUAAUGGCAUUACCAUUUACCACGCCACCCAAGAUACUUACUAGGAACCUCAAAGUAUUGUAUUCUUUUUCUCCAUCACACUCAUACUUAAUCAUCAAGUCCUUUUGAGCUUGUCUCCUCUUGAAUAUGUCCCUUCUUAAUUCCUGCUGCCUUCUUAGUAAAGGCCUUCAUUCUUUUUUCCCUAGUAAUAAUCUUUUCCAUAUGUUCCAGUUAAAAUACCAUGUUCUCCCUAUUCCUUAUUACAUAGCUAGCAUUCCUUGAAAAAAAACAAUUCUCUCAGGCCUCCAUACCUUUAGCAUGUUACCCACUCUGCCUCUGCUCUUCUGGAACUAGAACACUCAUCCUUGAAGGCUGGGCUUCUGUAUGAAGGUUGGUCCUGCCUCCUUACUUGAGGUGAAGCUUUGUACAUGCCUGUAUUACGGACAUCCUCUUAUUUAAGUGUUUGUCUCUUUCGUCAUUGGGACUCCAGCACCCAGCAUAGUCCCUAGUAUACUAGUUGGUGCUGAAUAAAUAGUAGCUAUUAUUAGAAAAGGAAGGGUGAAAUUGACAUGGGAGUUAGUAAAAUGUAUAUGGAAAUGAUUUUUAAAGGGAAAGGUAAUGAUUUUCUGGCAGGAAAAGCAGCAAUGACAAGAUUACUUAAGUCUUGUGAAAUAACACUUCUCUUCCUUGACCUGCUGCUUCCCUUUUUUACCACACACACACGCACACAUACCACAGCCCUUUGAGACUGAAAGCAGCUCUAUUGAGAAUAGUAGUGUCAACUGUAUUAUGUAGAAAUUCUAAAGUUUUUGGGAUUAUUUCAUAGCCCUGACCUUGCUACUUCUCUCCACUUUAUGUGGCAGGUUUAAUCUCAGGUCUCCCUCAUACACUUCUCAGCCUCAGCACCUAACCCUCACACAACACUCCAGUAUUGAUGCAGUCAAUCUUGUAUAACAUUUUUUGAAUGUCCAAUGUGCAAAGCACGAUGUUGGAAAUUAUACAGAGGUGAAUAAGACAAAAACUCUUGCUCUCAAAGAUGUCAGUCUUUUUCUUUGCAAGGAUAACACAUGUAGAGUAAAAUGCAUAAAGGGGACUAAUUUUAAAUGUACAGCUUAAUUAAUUUUUAUGUAUGUUAACACCCAUGUCACCACCAUGUUUAGGACAUUUCCAGCACCCCUGAAAUUUCCUUCAUGCCCCUUCCCAGUCUGUACCUACACCUCUAAAUCUAUUUUCAAUCUUAAUGGCCUUUUAAAUAACUGGGCUUCUCACAACCAUAGUGAACAGAAACAGCUGGGUUGUCAACGUCUAACCUAAUACUUCAGGAAAACUCAUGAUGGUUUCCAUGUUAAGAGAGACAUGGAGCAGGGCACUGGCAUGGUGGAUGGAUCACGCCUGUAAUCCCAGCACUUUGGGAGGCCGAGGUAGGGGGAUUGCUUGAGCCCAGGAGUUCAAGACUAGCCUGGGUAAUAUAAGGAAAACCUGUCUCUGCAAAAAAAAAAAAAAAAAGAGGAUACAACCAAAUGGAAGAACAUUCCAUGCUCAUGGGUAGGAAGAAUCAAUAUCGUGAAAAUGGCCAUACUGCCCAAGGUAAUUUACAGAUUCAGUGCCAUCCCCAUCAAGCUACCAAUGCCUUUCUUCACAGAAUUGGAAAAAACUACUUUAAAGUUCAUAUGGAACCAAAAAAGAGCCCAUAUCGCCAAGUCAAUCCUAAGCCAAAAGAACAAAGCUGGAGGCAUCACACUACCUGACUUCAAACUAUACUACAAGGCUACAGUAACCAAAACAGCAUGGUACUGGUACCAAAACAGAGAUAUAGAUCACUGGAACAGAACAGAGCCCUCAGAAAUAACGCCGCAUAUCUACAACUAUCUGAUCUUUGACAAACCUGAGAAAAACAAGCAAUGGGGAAAGGAUUCCCUAUUUAAUAAAUGGUGCUGGGAAAACUGGCUAGCCAUAUGUAGAAAGCUGAAACUGGAUCCCUUCCUUACACCUUAUACAAAAAUCAAUUCAAGAUGGAUUAAAGACUUAAACGUUAGACCUAAAACCAUAAAAACCCUAGAAGAAAACCUAGGCAUUACCAUUCAGGACAUAGGCAUGGGCAAGGACUUCAUGUCUAAAACACCAAAAGCAAUGGCAACAAAAGCCAAAAUUGACAAAUGGGAUCUAAUUAAACUAAAGAGCUGCUGCACAGCAAAAGAAACUACCAUCAGAGUGAACAGGCAACCUACAAAAUGGGAGAAAAUUUUCGCAACCUACUUAUCUGACAAAGGGCUAAUAUCCAGAAUCUACAAUGAACUCAAACAAAUUUACAAGAAAAAAACAACCCCAUCAAAAAGUGGGCGAAGGACAUGAACAGACACUUCUCAAAAGAAGACAUUUAUGCAGCCAAAAAACACAUGAAAAAAUGCUCAUCAUGACUGGCCAUCAGAGAAAUGCAAAUCAAAACCACAAUGAGAUACCAUCUCACACCAGUUAGAAUGGCAAUCAUUAAAAAGUCAGGAGACAACAGGUGCUGGAGAGGAUGUGGAGAAAUAGGAACACUUUUACACUGUUGGUGGGACUGUAAACUAGUUCAACCAUUGUGGAAGUCAGUGUGGCGAUUCCUCAGGGAUGUAGAACUGGAAAUACCGUUUGACCCAGCCAUCCCAUUACUGGGUAUAUACCCAAAGGACUAUAAAUCAUGCUGCUAUAAAGACACAUGCACACGUAUGUUUAUUGCGGCAUUAUUCACAAUAGCAAAGACUUGGAACCAACCCAAAUGUCCAACAAUGAUAGACUGGAUUAAGAAAAUGUGGCACAUAUACACCAUGGAAUACUAUGCAGCCAUAAAAAAUGAUGAAUUCAUGUCCUUUGUAGGGACAUGGAUGAAAUUGGAAAACAUCAUUCUCAGUAAACUAUCGCAAGAACAAGAAACCAAACACCACAUAUUCUCACUCAUAGGUGGGAAUUGAACAAUGAGAACACAUGGACACAGGAAGGGGAAUAUCACACUGGGGACUGUUGUGGGGUGGGGGGAGGGGGGAGGGAUAGCAUUGGGAGAUAUACCUAAUGCUAGAUGACGAGUUAGUGGGUGCAGUGCACCAGCAUGGCACAUGUAUACAUAUGUAAGUAACCUGCACAAUGUGCACAUGUACCCUAAAGCUUAAAGUAUAAUAAAAAAUAAAUAAAUAAAUAAAUAAGAAAAAGAAAGCCAGGCAUGGUGACAUGUGCCUGUGGUCCCAGCUAUUAGGGAGGCUGAGGUGGGAGGAUCCCUUGAACCCAGGAGGUUGAGUCUGUAGUGAGCAGUGAUUACGCCACUGCACUCCAGCCUGGGCAAGACCCUGUCUCAAAAAAAAAAAAGACUUAGAAUUGGUGAUCCAGGCCGCCUAAUGGCAUCAAAUAAUUUGUUAUAUCUUUAAUUUAUUGAAGGAUCACCACAUGCUUUUAAAUAGCAUGGAGAAAUGGAAAGAAUAGGGACUUUUUACUCAGGUAAUACCCAGCCUGCUACCUAACAGGUUGUGUUGUACUAAAUAAAAUGGUACAUAAGAAGAAACACUGUAAAUUAUAUAGUGCGAAUCAAAUAUUGUUAAUAAACCAAUAUCUGUAUAUCCUAUGUCCCGGAUUAAUCUUUAAUUUAGAUACUCCUUCUAGUUAUCUAAUACACAGCAGAGUGAGAAAAAUCAUUAUGGAUUAGGUUCUUUAGUAAGAAACCUGAGAUGGACUUCUCAUUAGCAUUAACUAGUUAUUGCCCAGCUUUGGAGAGCCUUCUUUUGGCUUAUCAUUUAUUAUAAGCCCAGAAAUAGGUGACUAAUCAGAGAUAAAUGUAUGGGUUGUCUGUAUCUAGUUUUAUGCCUUUUUUUUGCCUAAGACGUAGUCAAAUUAAUAUUUUAACUAAUACAUCUUAGCAGAGUUUAGUUAAGCACAAAGUUAACAGUGGGUAGGAUUGAAUCUUGAAAGUAAUCAUGUCUGUAAUGUUUUUCAUGCAUGCAAAAAGCACAGACAAAACCACUCAUGCCCUAUUAAUAAACAAAAUACAGAUCAAAGUUUUCAAAAGUAAUCACUCUAUUUAUUCUAAAUGUCUGUGGCUUUAGGAAAAUACCACCAGCUAGUACUUACCUAUUUAAAGAUGUAGAAUUUAUUAUCCUCUAAUAUUCUUAUCAGUUGUUUCCACAACUUUAGUUUACUAUUGGACUUUCAAAAAUUUAAAGAAUUACAAGUAAAAUUCAUUAAACACUUGUGUGUGAAUAGUAAUACACAGUAAUUAGUACAGCAUGUUGCUUCUUCAACAAAUUGAGUUUUCAGGGAAAUCAGCAAGUAAAUGAAAUAUAAAUUUUUGGUAAAAGUAUCAAACAUUCAUCUUGCCCAUUUUUCCUCUUAAACUUUAUUAUCUAAUCAAACAUAGUUUUCCAUAAGAUGUAAUAAAAUAUAGAUAAGGUUGGAAUAUUUGAGGAUCCAUUUGUGGAACUGAAUUUAAUGAGACUUCAUUGGUGAUACACUCAAUUUUUACUGGGUAAUUAGCUAAUAAUGUUGGUCACUGUCUCACAGUUCAAGUAGCUUUAAGAUGAUGUGGCAAGGAAAACACAAAGCUUUUGGGUAACCAGCGUUCUUAAAUGUAUGGUUUUUGACCAGGUGAACCCUUUAGAAGUGAUUUCUGUUUUAAAAGUAUGUACUUAAAAUACCUUUGGCUGUGAUGAAUGUAGAUCCCAGCAGAAUACCAAAAUCCUAUUUUUUUUGACUGAGUAUUUGUAGAUGCUUAAUGACUGAAAUGAAUUUGGAGGCACUGAUGAAAGUGAUUUUUUUAAAGUUCUCAGGUACUGUUCAAUUAUUUAAUGUUAAGUUUAGUAUCAAGAUACAGUUGUUUUUAAAAUGCCAAAAUGCUGUUUAUUAUACAGAAUAUUUUAUUACAUUUGCAAUAUCUUUGUAUAUAGUGAUUUUUUUCUUGAUAAUAAAUGGAAAAAUUCUAAAACA